CAGAACCUAGCUUUCCUGCCUGCCCCCAGGGCUAAUCCAGAGGUGGGGGAGGGGCUAAAGACACUGGGCUCUGCCAGGGGCCUUGGAUGAGCUUAUCAUGGAACAUAAGAAAAAUAAAACAGAUGUCAGCCUGUGUAUGAAGAAUUCAUCCACAAGAUUUGAGCAGACCGAAGACUGUGAGACUUCCUCCCCACAGUGAGCUAAAAGGACGCUUUUGUCAGAGUGGGGAAAUAAAAGGGCUUUAUGGGAAGGAAGAUAAGAACAGAUGAGUCAGAGGUUUCUGCUUAAUGCUCACUCUUCAAUUCUUUCCCGAGCAAAACCAAGAAUCUUCUUGGGCUAAGCCCCAAUUUGGGGUUCACCUGCCUUGCAGCAACAUGGCACCAAACAUGCGGCAGAAGAGAGAAAACGACAGCAUGAGAGACGGAGAAAGAAAUGGCCAGUUGGCAAGGUGGUAAUGAGAGACAGCAGUUGGCAAGACAGUGAGAGACAGCAAGAGAUGGCAAGUGACAGUUAUUGUUAAGAUGACAAAUGGAGAGAUGGCAAGAAAUAGAGAAGCAGUCAGUGAUGGAGGCUGCAAGAGUUGUAACACUAACCAAAGGCUCUUUUUAGAAUCAUCGUUUUCCCUGGCAGGUGGUACAGCCAAGCAGACAGGCAAGUAAGUGGCCAUACUGCUACUGCCUCAUGUAGGAUCCGGCAGGCUGGUGGGUUAUCAGUCCUCACGUGGGACCCUCCCACCAUGGCAGCUGAGCACAUCCAAGCUGGGGGAUCCUGAAGAGACCUUCACCUGGGUGCCACGUGGAAGAUUGGCCAGCACCAUUUUGACUCCUGUGGAUGGGAUAACGAGAACUCAGCGCCCAUCUUGAACAUGUCUUCAUCUUCUGGAAGCUCUGGAGUGCACACCUCUUGGAACCAAGGCCUACCAAGCAUUCAGCACUUUCCUCACAGCGCAGAGAUGCUGGGGUCCCCUUUGGUGUCUGUUGAGGCGCCGGGGCAGAAUGUGAAUGAAGGGGGGCCACAGUUCAGUAUGCCACUGCCUGAGCGUGGUAUGAGCUACUGCCCCCAAGCGACUCUCACUCCUUCCCGGAUGAUUUACUGUCAGAGAAUGUCUCCCCCUCAGCAAGAGAUGACGAUUUUCAGUGGGCCCCAACUAAUGCCCGUAGGAGAGCCCAAUAUUCCAAGGGUAGCCAGGCCCUUCGGUGGGAAUCUAAGGAUGCCCCCCAAUGGGCUGCCAGUCUCGGCUUCCACUGGAAUCCCAAUAAUGUCCCACACUGGGAACCCUCCAGUGCCUUACCCUGGCCUCUCGACAGUACCUUCUGACGAAACAUUGUUGGGCCCGACUGUGCCUUCCACUGAGGCCCAGGCAGUGCUCCCCUCCAUGGCUCAGAUGUUGCCCCCGCAAGAUGCCCAUGACCUUGGGAUGCCCCCAGCUGAGUCCCAGUCAUUGCUGGUUUUAGGAUCUCAGGACUCUCUUGUCAGUCAGCCAGACUCUCAAGAAGGCCCAUUUCUACCAGAGCAGCCCGGACCUGCUCCACAGACAGUAGAGAAGAACUCCAGGCCUCAGGAAGGGACUGGUAGAAGGGGCUCCUCAGAGGCAAGGCCUUACUGCUGCAACUACGAGAACUGCGGAAAAGCUUAUACCAAACGCUCCCACCUCGUGAGCCACCAGCGCAAGCACACAGGUGAGAGGCCAUAUUCUUGCAACUGGGAAAGUUGUUCAUGGUCUUUCUUCCGUUCUGAUGAGCUUAGACGACAUAUGCGGGUACACACCAGAUAUCGACCAUAUAAAUGUGAUCAGUGCAGCCGGGAGUUCAUGAGGUCUGACCAUCUCAAGCAACACCAGAAGACUCAUCGGCCGGGACCCUCAGACCCACAGGCCAACAACAACAAUGGAGAGCAGGACAGUCCUCCUGCUGCUGGUCCUUAGGUGAAUGAAGAAGGAAGAGGAUUCCAGGCUGAGAGCACUGGACGUGGCAACUGUUCAGAGGAGAGGCAGUCUUCAAGUUCUACAUUCAUUCAGAAAAAUGUUUUUUGAGCCUACAAUACUGAGCGCAACAAGGCUGUGGAGACCCAUGGUGAGGAGCAUGGAGUUAACUAAAGGAUGUGUCAGGGAAGAAAGACUUCUCAAGGAGGUGCCUCCAUCAGACCCAAAGGACUCAUGGGGGCUAGCUGCACCUCACAUUUCUUGGACAUAUACCGUUGGACAUGUCUAUCUUCUGGAAACUAUGGCAUGGACAGUAAGGAUUCAGAAGUGCAUGAAGGCACCCUGCCUCUGCAGAGCAGAAAGAUCAUAGACAACAUUUAUGAAUGUGCCCAGUGCUGCCAAGAAGAGAAGCCGGUCCUCUGCAGGCUCAAGCCUAUCUGGGCCUCUGGGGAAGCCCCACAGCCUUGGCUGUGCCUGCCCCUGCCCUCUCACCCCUACCCUGACCUUGUCCUACUUCACUGCCUUUGUCUGUGUUACUAGUGGCCCCAGUAUACCUGGGAUGGACAUCCAGGUGCCCUUCAUCCAAGCUCCUAUGUGAGGGGAAUGGACAUUAUUAAAAGAACAGGGGCAGAAGUGGCUCAUUUAUGACCCAUUCACUAGCCCCAGGGAUUGAAGUCUUGGGUACUCAAAGUGUCUUUCUACCAGGGCACCAGAUCCCUUCCAUGGAGCAGGUCAUCUCGGGUUCACUGGGCCAGGGAUGGUCUCUGUUCCCCAGCCCACCUGGCUCACACACAGCCUCAUGGGUAGGGUCAGCAAACCAGAUGGCUUGUUGUUGGAAUGUAGGAUGAGAGGCCUGCUUGGUGACCUAGCAUUUUCACCAAGAAGUGGACGUGGAGAGGACCAGAGUGAUCAAGGGUGUAUGAUGUGCACUACAAUGGUGGGCAAAACAGGCUCCUGCUCUUGUGGAGGUCACAAUCUAGCGGAGAAAGGAUGUUACUAGAAGUACACAAAUUGGGCCCGGCGCGAUGGCUCACGCCUGUAAUCCCAGCACUUUUGGAGGCCGAGGCAGGCGGAUCAUUUGAGGUUAGAGAUUCGAGACCAGCCGGGCCAACAUGGUGAAACCCCAUCUCUACAAAAAAUACAAAAAUUAGCCUGGCAUAUGGCGGGUACCGUAAUCCUAGCUACUCGGGAGACUGACGGGAGAAUCGCUUGAACCCAGGAGGCGGAGGUUGCAGUGAGCUCAGAUCUCACCAUUGCACUCCAGCCUGGGCGACUGAGCGAGACUCUAUCUCAAAACAAUCAAAACAAAAAAGACCUGUGGACUCUAGUAGAUUUUGAAUCCUGCCUCUGCCAUUUCCUGGCUAUGAGGUGUCUUGAGAAAUUUACUUGUCACUCUUGCUUCUGAUAGUAAAGGGGAUGGUGCGAUAGAUUCAAGAUGGAGAGAUAAGGUUAAGUGUUUUCUUUGGCUGCAACAUGGAGAUUAGAUUAGAGCAAGGAUGUAAGGGAGAGGAAGGGACAUAGCAGUAUUUCAGGUGAGAGUCAAGGUGGCUUUGGCUAGGGUGUGAGAGUGGAGGUAGGGAGAAGUAGGAAAGUGAUAGUUAACUGGAUUUGUUAGGUGAGGGUGAGGCCAAGGGUGACUUCCAGGUUCCUGACUUGUGUUAUAAGUAACACAGAAGAAGAAUGGAUGAACUUGAUUCGUUUUCCAUUGAUUGUGAUAUCUAUCAUACCUGCAAAAAAUAUUUUGUAUAUAUCCAAUUUAAUAAUAAAUGCACUCAUGUUAGGAAGGUCAAAAAAAAGGAAAAAAGAAAAAUAAUAAAAAAUAAUAAAAAUCCUUAGGAUAACUUGAGGCCAGGAGUUUGAGACCAGUGUGACCUUGUCUCUGUAAAAAAUAAAAUUAAAAGAAAAA